GACAGAGUCAGCUGAGCUCAGCUUCAAGGGGACCAGGUAGGAGAUGUGCCAACGUUCUUGGGCAAGGGUGGCAAUGGGGCUCCUGGGCUGUAGGCAGGCAGUGGGGAAGGUGUCAUAGGUAAAUGUCAUCUGGAGACACUGUGACCAGGGCACUAGGAGAGGCGAAGGCACUGUGGGGAGAGACACUCCUCUUCCAGGGAUAUAGCUGUGAUGACGAGUCAGAAGACACUUUGGGUCUGGGUAUCUUCCCACUUUGGAUAGUGCUGGGAGGCCUCCACCCUCUUCAGCCAGCCAGGCUCUUAGGGACAGAGUGAGCUGCAGAGUGAGUACAACCCAAAUACACGGGCUGCCUGCCUGAGCCCCAGCACUGCCUGCUGCCCACCACUUCCCAAGCUGGACCAAGGGAGCUUGGGUAGGGGCCAGGCUAGCCUGAGUGCACCCAGAUGCGCUUCUGUCAGCUCUCCCUAGUGCUUCAACCACUGCUCUCCCUGCUCUACUUUUUUUGCUCCAGCUCAGGGAUGGGGGUGGGCAGGGAAAUCCUGCCACCCUCACUUCUCCCCUUCCCAUCUCCAGGGGGGCCAUGGCCAGUACAGAGUCCUCCCUGUUGAGAUCCCUAGGCCUCAGCCCAGGUCCUGGCAGCAGUGAGGUGGAGCUGGACUGUUGGUUUGAUGAGGAUUUCAAGUUCAUCCUGCUGCCUGUGAGCUAUGCAGUUGUCUUUGUGCUGGGCUUGGGCCUUAACGCCCCAACCCUAUGGCUCUUCAUCUUCCGCCUCCGACCCUGGGAUGCAACGGCCACCUACAUGUUCCACCUGGCAUUGUCAGACACCUUGUAUGUGCUGUCGCUGCCCACCCUCAUCUACUAUUAUGCAGCCCACAACCACUGGCCCUUUGGCACUGAGAUCUGCAAGUUCGUCCGCUUUCUUUUCUAUUGGAACCUCUACUGCAGUGUCCUUUUCCUCACCUGCAUCAGCGUGCACCGCUACCUGGGCAUCUGCCACCCACUUCGGGCACUACGCUGGGGCCGCCCUCGCCUCGCAGGCCUUCUCUGCCUGGCAGUUUGGUUGGUCGUAGCCGGCUGCCUCGUGCCCAACCUGUUCUUUGUCACAACCAGCAACAAAGGGACCACCGUCCUGUGCCAUGACACCACUCGGCCUGAAGAGUUUGACCACUAUGUGCACUUCAGCUCGGCGGUCAUGGGGCUGCUCUUUGGCGUGCCCUGCCUGGUCACUCUUGUUUGCUAUGGACUCAUGGCUCGUCGCCUGUAUCAGCCCUUGCCAGGCUCUGCACAGUCGUCUUCUCGCCUCCGCUCUCUCCGCACCAUAGCUGUGGUGCUGACUGUCUUUGCUGUCUGCUUCGUGCCUUUCCACAUCACCCGCACCAUUUACUACCUGGCCAGGCUGUUGGAAGCUGACUGCCGAGUACUGAACAUUGUCAACGUGGUCUAUAAAGUGACUCGGCCCCUGGCCAGUGCCAACAGCUGCCUGGAUCCUGUGCUCUACUUGCUCACUGGGGACAAAUAUCGACGUCAGCUCCGUCAGCUCUGUGGUGGUGGCAAGCCCCAGCCCCGCACGGCUGCCUCUUCCCUGGCACUAGUGUCCCUGCCUGAGGAUAGCAGCUGCAGGUGGGCGGCCACCCCCCAGGACAGUAGCUGCUCUACUCCUAGGGCAGAUAGAUUGUAACACGGGAAGCCGGGAAGUGAGAGAAAAGGGGAUGAGUGCAGGGCAGAGGUGAGGGAACCCAAUAGUGAUACCUGGUAAGGUGCUUCUUCCUCUUUUCCAGGCUCUGGAGAGAAGCCCUCACCCUGAGGGUUGCAGGGAGGCAGGGAUAUCAUGGGUGACCUCAUCUCUCAUAACCCCUUCAGUUGCCGACUCUUUUUAGCCAAUGCCAAUCUUCUACUCCUUUCUCGUUGUUUCUGUUCCUUCCUGGGGCCAUUGGUCCUACAAUCUUCCUGAAAAUCUUCCCCAGUCCUCUUUCCCUGUCCCAUUUCCCCCACAGCCUCCUAUAGCAUGUGUUUCUCUACCCAGACCAGAGCAUUCAGCU